GGAGGGGCGUAGGGCUCUGCGACGCGCAGCGCGCUAGGACGGUGGCACGAGGUGUGUGGCGCUGGCCGCGUGGCCUUACAACCCUCGCUAUCACUACCACCCAGUGCAUGUGGGUGCUGAAGCCCGCAGGGAUACAAGGGCGCCAGGGGCUGCCUGCAAAGUCUAUGCUGGCGGAGGUGGCCGUGACGGGAAGUCCUGACUUUGGGCCUCCCGGAUCCCCACGGUCCAUUCCCAGAAACCCUCGCGCCUAGGAGUCUUUCUUCAAAGGAGUUGGGCCAGGGCGCCCAAGCGUGCGGGCCACCCCGCUUUGCAGGGCUCUCCCUGAAGCCCUGCUUUCUCCGCCAACACCGAUUCCCUUGCUUCUGGAUGGGGAGGUGAAGCACUCAGCCGUUGGCCCACCUGCGCAUCUUUGCUCAGCCUCCUGACUCAACGCUGAACAUUGAGAGGAAGCAAGGCAGGCUGGACAGAGGACAAGCACAGAGAAGGCAACAGGAGCAAAGUCUACCGAAAAGCUAUUUCAAGUUGGGUCUGGAGGCAAGGCCAGGCGAUCGUGGAUUGAGAAGCUUCCCCAGGGCCCUUGCAACAGCUGCCAUCCUCCAUCCACAUCUCUCUCACUGGGAUGGGAAUUUUUUUUUUUUUUUUGAGACGGAGUCUCGCUCUGUCGCCCAGGCUGGAGUGCAGUGGCUCUAUCUACAACCUCUGCCUCCCAGGUUCAAGCGAUUCUCCCACCUCAGCCUCCUGAGUAGCUGAGAUUACAGGCGCCUGCCACCAUGCCCGGCUAAUUUUCGUAUUUUUGUAGAGACGGGGAGUCACCAUGUUGGCCAGGCUGGUCUCAAACUCCUAACCUCAGGUGAUCCACCCGCCUCGGCCUCCCAAAGUGCUGGGAUUACAGGCGUGAGCCACCCCGCCCAGCCAAGCCCGCCUUCUCUUAAUUUACCUUUUCAUUCUUCUUUCCUGAUAGUUUUGACGUGAACUGUUCGGACCCUCAGUGCUACCUGAUAGAAAACUGCAUUCCAGGAAAGGAACACAGCUGUGCAGAGUCUGAUCUGUGAAAACCUAGAAGGUUUGUUAAGACUCUUGCCAACAUGUGCUCUCCUGCCAGUCCCAAAAUCCUAUACAGGAACCCCCGGUUCCUCAGGUUAGCUUUUCUGCAGCUUCAUCACCAGCAGCAGAGUGAUGUGUUCUGUGAUGUCCUUCUGCAGGCAGAAGGUGAGGCAGUUCCAGCUCACUGCUGCAUCCUGUCAGCUUGUAGCCCCUUCUUCACAGAGCGCCUGGAGCGGGAGAGGCCAGCUCAGGGUGGGAAGGUGGUGCUAGAGCUGGGUGGCCUGAAGAUCAGCACACUUAGGAAGCUGGUGGACUUCUUGUAUACCUCAGAAAUGGAAGUAUCUCAAGAAGAAGCCCAGGAUGUGCUAUCUGCUGCCCGUCAGCUCCGUGUGUCUGAGCUGGAAUCCCUUCAGCUUGAGGGUGGAAAGUUGGUGAAGGCCCCACAGGGCCGAAGGCUGAACCGAGAGUGCUUACAACCAACAAGUGCUGCACCAAUCUCUGCCAGAGUGGUGACACCCAGCCACCACCCUCACACCCCACUGCCCACUAAUCAAACUCCUUGUCCUCUUGGGGCAAUAAGAUUGAAGUCCUUGGGGAAGGAAGAGGGGCCCCAGGAAAACAACCGACAGAAUGCAGACAAUUUGUCUGGCACUCUUCUGCUCAAGAGGAAGGCCAGAGCCUGCCCAACUCCACAAGAAAAAAACUCUUCACCAUCAAGCCAUAGUCAAGAGCCUAGAGAGAACAAGAAUGACACUGCCCUUGAUCCUACAGUGCUCUCCCCACCCAGCUUGUACCCCUCUGUGGACAAACACCUGUUGCCCAGAAAGAUCAGGCUCAGUCGCUCAAAGCCAUCUCCUGGUAUCUGUACAUCAAAGCCUUCCAGCAUUUUAAGUGGAUCUAGCUCAGUGCCUGCAACCCCUGGCCGGCGUCUUUGGCGGCAGAGGAGUGUAAAUAAAGAAACACCAGAGGACAAGCCAAAACCAGGCAGAGCUAGUCCUCUGCAGAGCACCCCAAACCCAUCUGGUCUGGGAAAGACAGGUGGGAGCAGGAAGCGGAGCCCUGAAGUCAGGGCACCUAACUCAGACUCUGCAGAGGAGGGGCAGGUUGGGAGAGUUAAACUUAGGAAGAUUGUCAAUGGGACUUGCUGGGAAGUGGUACAAGAGACUCCUCUCAAAAACACUCAAGAUAGCCCCCAGAUCCCAGAUCCCGGAGGAGACUUCCAAGAGCCUUCAGGAACUCAGCCAUUCUCCAGUAAUGAGCAGGAAAUGUCACCUACUAGAACAGAACUGUGUCAGGACUCCCCCAUGUGCACUAAGCUACAAGACAUUCUGGUCUCUGCUAGCCACUCCCCAGACCACCCAGUGGUGAAGUCAGAGUUUGAGUCCAGUCCAGAACUGGUAGAGAAGGAACCUAUGUUGGCUAUUGACUGCAGAGAACCCUAUGCAUUUGACACAGCUCUGCUGGAGCAGCCCUGUGAGGCUGAGGAGUACCGAAUCACAAGUGCUGCUGCCACCAGUGAGCUGGAGGAGAUCCUGGACUUCAUGCUCUGUGGCUCAGACAUUGAACCACCUAUAGGGUCUCUGGAGAGUCCAGGGGCUGAGGGCUGCAGAACGCCUACCUACCAUCUGACAGAAACAGGAAAGAACUGGAUUGAAGGGGAAGAAUGGUGUCUACCAGACAUGGAACUCUGGCCCAGGGAGCUCACAGAAUUGGAAAAGGAACCUGCUGGUGAGAACAGAGGGCCAACUGAGCUCCUUAGCCCCCUUGUCAUGCCCUCUGAGGUGAGUGAAGUGCUUUCAGUAGGAGGCCGUUGGACACCAGACCUUGAAAUUACCAGCUCCCAGCCACUGGAUGGUCAGGAAGACAAACUUCUCCAUGUCAGCUCCCUUGAUACUCCCCAGAGGUCUUAUGGGGACCUCUCACCUCCCUGCUCAAACUGGGUGGAGACUGGGCUGGAAGUCUCCUUGACUACAGAUGAGUUAUUAUACCCUUCUCCCAAGGCAGGCAAGGAGGUAUCUGGUCACUCUGAACUACUAGGCUCACUUCCUGCCAGCUCUGAAGAGGAAGAGAUUGAUGUGGUGGACUGGACAGCAGAGGGGAGGCUGGUACCCACUACUGUUCCCUCCGUGUGGCCUGACCCUUCCUCAGAGUCAGAAACAGAGGUAGAUAUACUAACAUAGUGGAGAGGGGAGGGCAGGUUAGGGGCCUUGGGAGGGUGGGAAAUGUUAGCUAGCAAAAGGCUUACUGGCAGAGAAGCUGGCACGUGCCCUCAGCACAAGAGGCAGGUGUACCCUGGCUCUUUGUAGGUCCCUUCCUCCCUUCCCUAAGCCUCAGAAGCCAGGCAGAAGCCAAGGGUACCAUAGAUAGAAAAUUAUGAACUUGUACCAUCUUAUUUGUAAUCUAUUUUCCGGUUAGUGACAACUGAAACAAACUGUGUGCUCCCCAAUUCUGGUGGGUCAUAGGUAACAGCCAAGGCCAGAUCUCUCAGGUCAUAAGGCAUCCAGUCACUGGUAAUUUAGGAAAAGCUGAGAAAGAACACCCUCCUCUGUGGUGGGGUAUUGUUUAAGAAAAUGUUCCAGAGGAAGGUGUGAAGCAGUGUUGGGUGGAAUACUAAGUGGGUGGGAGUGAUGGAUGCUGUCCAGCACCCAACGUGGGGCUUAUUCACUGCCAGUAUUAGGAAGUCUAGCUAAAACCUCUGCAGGGGCCAAGAAGAUGUACUUCCAUCAUUACUUCCAAAAAGUAAGUUGAAAAAGAUACAGUUGCUUUUUUAAAAAAUAAAUUAUUUACUUUGCUCCCAUAA